CUGUCACCUUCACAGCAUGAGGUGCCUGUGCUUCCCUGAGCUCUGGAAUGUUCUGGGGCCAGCGGCUGUGCUUAGCUUCUGCCAGCACGUCCACACGGCCCGUUCCCUCGUCUCAUGUCAGGACCCCUGGGAUUACGGGACCAGCAGAGCUGCCUUCUCUGGCCACUGCCCACACCUGUGGGCCCCUGUGGCAUCCAGGCCACUUGCUCUGGGGCGUUUGGGGGGCCGGGGAGUGGGUGGAGCUGGCACCAGCUUGAUCCAGGCUCCUCAUGCCUGGCCCUGGGGUCUGUUUGUGCUCCAAGUGCCAAGAGUGCCACCCUACCCCUCCUCAUCUGCUUCCCAUGAGUGGGGCCGGGGCUGGGUGAGAGGCCCCCAGAAGCUGCCCCUGUGCACCUCACCAGCCCGUCACUCUUCUUCUAAAGUAACAAAAACAAGUACCUCAGUUCUCACGGGGGCUGGGGCCCAGGGUUGCUGUGCUGUCUCUCUAGUUACCAGGGUUGGCUCCUUCCUCUCAGCCUCCUUCCGGCAGGAGGUUAUAUCUGAGAGGGAGGAGGAGAACCAUGUCCAGAUACAUGGGGGCAGUGGGGAUGGGCUGAGCAUCAGGACACAGCCUCCCCCAUUUCUGUGUGUGUAA